ACCCUCAGCAGAGACAGACCCCAGAUCUGGGCCCAGGACUUUGUGCAGGGAGGGGAAAUGCAGACUGGACUCUGAAAUGGGCAUGUACAGAGACGAAGAGACCCCAACAUGCUUCAGGCUUUGAGUGGAGAGGACACAGCCUCUGCUGGGACAGGGAAUAGAGGGAUGUGGAGUCCCUGAAGAUGCUUUUGGACAAUGGUCUGAGGUUGGGACAGUGGCAGGAGAUACCAUUCACCCAGGAUCUCCAGGACAAGAGAUCAGCCUGGCAGUUACAUGUGUUUUUUUUCAAACUGGUUGCCAGGUUGGCAUGAACGAUGACAUCAGAGAUUCCGACCUUCCUGAUUGGAGGGACCGGACUCCGUGGUGCCUGGAGAUCAGUUGGACAACAGUAUCUUCUCAGAGCUGUUCUCUACUCCUGACUUCUCCUAGGCUUGAGAAUUGAUAACAUACUCUUCUGGAUCCUAGAAGUGUCCAGAAGAAGGCCAUGGACAGAACGGAGACUAGGUUCCGUAAGAGGGGACAGAUUACGGGAAAGAUCACGACCAGCCGUCAACCGCACCCCCAGAAUGAGCAGAGUCCCCAGCGGAGCACCUCGGGGUACCCCCUCCAGGAGGUGGUGGAUGAUGAAAUGUUGGGACCAUCAGCCCCUGGGGUAGAUCCCAGCCCCCCAUGUAGGUCCCUUGGCUGGAAAAGGAAGAGGGAGUGGUCAGAUGAAUCUGAGGAGGAGCCGGAGAAGGAGCUCGCCCCUGAGCCUGAGGAGACCUGGGUAGUGGAGAUGCUGUGUGGGCUCAAGAUGAAGCUGAAGCAACAGCGAGUGUCACCCAUCCUCCCUGAGCACCACAAGGACUUCAACAGUCAGCUUGCCCCUGGGGUAGAUCCCAGCCCCCCGCAUAGGUCCUUUUGCUGGAAAAGGAAGAUGGAGUGGUGGGACGAAUCUGAGGAGUCGUUGGAGGAGGAGCCACGGAAGGUGCUCGCCCCUGAGCCUGAGGAGAUCUGGGUGGCGGAGAUGCUGUGUGGCCUCAAGAUGAAGCUGAAGCGACGGCGAGUGUCGCUCGUGCUCCCUGAGCACCACGAGGCCUUCAACAGGCUGCUUGAGGAUCCUGUCAUUAAAAGAUUCUUGGCCUGGGACAAAGAUCUGAGGGUGUCGGACAAGUAUCUCCUGGCUAUGGUCAUAGCGUAUUUCAGCCGGGCCGGCUUCCCCUCCUGGCAAUACCAACGCAUUCAUUUCUUCCUGGCUCUCUACCUGGCCAAUGACAUGGAGGAGGACGACGAGGACUCCAAACAAAACAUCUUCCACUUCCUGUAUAGGAAGAACCGCUCUCGCAUACCCUUGCUCCGUAAGCCUUGGUUCCAGUUAGGCCAUUCCAUGAACCCGAGGGCCAGGAAGAACCGCUCUCGCAUACCCUUGCUCCGUAAGCGUCGGUUCCAGUUAUACCGUUCCACGAACCCGAGGGCCAGGAAGAACCGCUCUCGCAUACCCUUGCUCCGUAAGCGUCGGUUCCAGUUAUACCGUUCCAUGAACUCGAGGGCCAGGAAGAACCGCUCUCAGAUAGUCCUGUUCCAGAAACGACGGUUCCACUUCUUCUGUUCCAUGAGCUGCAGGGCUUGGGUUUCCCCAGAGGAGUUGGAGGAGGUGAGUGGGGCCUGGGGAGGUGGAGGAGGUGGGGAGGAAUUGGGUGGGCUGGAGGCUGGAUGAGGGGAGAGAGGGGUAUCCUGGCGAGUCCCCGUCUUCUCAAAGGGCGUUUGUUUUUCCAGAUCCAGGCUUAUGACCCAGAGCACUGGGUGUGGGCGCGAGAUCGCGCUCACCUUUCCUAGAGCUCCAGGGACCGGGGAGGCCUGAGGUCAUCGGCCUGAGAGAAGGUACAUCUGCAUCCUCUGGGGUAAAGGCAGAAUAUUGGGGUCUAUUUCGGAAAUCCGAAGAACCCAAUUGCUUGAUCUGGCUUCAAGCCUGGGCAACGUGGCGAGAUCCCCUCUCCACAAAAAUACAAAAACUAGCCAGGCGAUGUGGGACGCAUCUCUACUCCCAACUACUCAGGAGGCUGAGGCGGGAGGAUCGCUGGAGCCUGGAAGGUCGGGGCCGCACGGAGCCCUGAUCCUGCCACUGCACUCCAGUCUGGGCGACAGAGUGAGACCCUGCCUCAAAAAUAAUCAUAAAAACUGAGUUUGGGGAGGUUCAUUAUGAUUGACGCACUUGAGUUACUGAUUUGGGUCGAGGGUUCAGUGAAGCUUUGGUUUACAUCUUGUGCAGCUAACCACGUUGAGCACAGAGCAUGAGACUUCAUCAUGAGGAGGUAGGAUUAAGGAUUAGGCUUCUGGACUCGUGGUUCGUGAUGUUGUCACAUUAGAAACACAUCUAGCAUGGUUACAAGUUUAGAUCUUAAGUGACACAAAAGGCCCCAGCUGUGAUAAAGUCCAAAGCCACAUUCUCUGAGGGUGCCCUACUCCCUGGGCAGACCCACCCAAAGUCCUUGCUAUGAAGCAGAUCACUGGGGCUGACCUUGGGUGUAUUAAGUGAGUUUUGGAGUCGUGGUCACCAAAGUGUGAGUUUCACAGUUGAACACGAUGGUUCAGAAGCAGGGUAUAGAAUGAAAGGCAGCAGAUAAAAUUGCAUUUCUCAAUUGACAUGGGACGUGAAUAACUUUCCUGUCUAGAGAGCUGCCUCCUUGAAGUGUGACAUUGUCUCUCUCGCUUCCAGAACACCGGACCCAGGGGAGAUGUGGAUUUUCAGCGGGAACUUUAUUCCAAUGCUAAUGGCAGACACCAGGCAGGAGGAGAGGAACCAUUUGUGCAGAUCAUCUAGAAGAACCUGGACCAUUCUUGAUGGAGCUGAAUACAGUGAUCACGUUGUCCUCCUAGGAGCAGGGGUGGGGGGAGGGGGGUGGGGUCCUUCUAGGAGUCCUUGGAGAAAAGUAAGAAACCAGGAGCGUUUCCAGUUCCACCCUUUCCUGCGGCACCACCACCCUUUUUAUAUUGCUGAAUUCCAACCUCCCUGGGGCGGAACCUGGAGGUCCUGUUUCUUACGGACUUGCAGUCCAGGAGGAUUUGAAGGCACAAUGCAGGGGCUCAGAUUGGGACAGAAUUCUUUUGUGAAAUAUCAGUGCCACAGAUUGUAACAGAUAGCUUCAUGCACACUCUGCAUUUUAUUGGUUUGUAUGGAAAAUGUCGGCCAUUGAAUUAUUCAUAGAUUUAUUUCAAAUAGUUUGGAAAUUGUUGUACUUUUGAAAACAUGCUGUUCCUGUAGUUUUUUGAUGAGAGUUAUAGUUGUUAUAUAUACAUAAAGCUAAUUUUCUUUUCAUUUUUAAGAGACAAUUCUUUUUAUCCUAAAUAUUUUAUUAUCUUUAAAUUUGUUUCUGUAUUAUUACAUGUGCUCCUGAAGCGAGCACUCUUUUUAUCUAUGAUACUUCCAUAAUAAUCUCUUCUAUUUAUAGCUAUUGGUAGUUCCCCACCAGAAAAAAACAUAAUUCUGGUGAUAGAAAUUUUUAUUUGCUGUUUAGGUUUGUGACUGAAUUGUGAGAAUUCAGUUGUGAUUUUUAACAUGCCUCAGAUAUAUAUACUAACACGUCUAAUAUAUACUAUCUAUUUUAUUGGUUUAUUUUGAAAAACAUGGGUAUAGAAUUAUUUAAAUAUUAUUUUAUUUAUUUAAAUAUUUAUUAAAUAUAUUUAUUUAUUUAAAUAUUAUUAUUACUUUAAAUAUUAUUUUAAAUAUUUUGGAAAUACUGGUAUUUUUGAAUAGAUGCUGUUUCUAUAAAGCUGUGUGAUGGAUAUUAUAACUGUUAUAUACACAUACAUAUAAUUUUGUUUUCCUUUUUAAGAGAGGAUUCUUUUCAUCCUAAAUCUUUUACCUUUCAAUCUUUGUAUCUAUUAUUACACGUGCUGCUGAAGGGAGCAUGGUUUUUAUCUAUGAUACUUAGUUAACAUAUAUAUUACAUUUAUAGCUAUGUAGUAGUUCCCCUAAAUUCUUGUAAAAAUAAAUUUUUAUUUGAUAUUUCAUAUAUAUUUGAAAUGUGAGAAUUCAGAUGUAAUUUUUUACCUUGUUUUGGCAUGUUUGUAUGUUACUUUAAAGAGGAUGUGUGUUCUAAAGGAGGACAUGAGCUGUGUGUUUUCAAGAGAACAAUAGAGUGCGUCUCUUGGGGAAACAUAAUAAAAAUGAACUUUUCUCACCUUCACAGCAAUUGUGAUCAUAUUGGUCUGGAUUGAUUAUUUGCUGCCCAGUGAUAUUUUUCCUUAAUGGGGUUGUGGUUAUUUGAACAUAUUUAUUAGCUCUGGAAGAUAAUCCUGUGCUGUUUUUUAUGUAGAAAAAAACAUAAGGCUGGGUGCAGUGCUCACACCUACAAUCCCUGUGGUUUUGGAGGUCAUGGCGGGAGGAUCACCUGAGGCCAGGAGUUUGAGGCCAGCCUCAGCAACAUAGCAUCUACAUCUAUUUUUAAUUUUUAUUUUUUAAAGAAAAACAAUAGAAGAGAAGGCUGAUCCCAAGCUACAGGGUUUUUUUGUUUGUUUGUUUGUUUUGGAGACAGAGUCUUGCUCUGUCUCCCAGGCUGGAGUGCAGUGGCACAACCUCGGCUCCCUGCAACUUUCACCUCUGGGUUCAAACAAAUUCUCCUGCCUCAGCCUCCCAAGUAGCUGGGACUACAGGCACCCGUCUGUACGUCCGACUAACUUUUGUAAAAAUAGUAGAGACAAGGUUUCACCAUGUUGGCCAGGCUGGUCUCGAACUCCUGACUUCAAGUGAUCCACCUACCUCGGCCUCCCAAAGUGCUGGGAUUACAGGCAUGAGCUACUGCGCCCAGAUGCCAAGCUAGAGUUUUAAGGCAGGAAAUGAGAGAAAGAUAUUGAGAGAGGAAAACCAGGUGGUAAGAAAACUCUAAAGGUGGCCGGGCGUGGUGGCUCACGCCCAUGAUCCCAGCAGGAGUUUGAGACCAGCCUGGCCAACAUGGUGAAACCCUGUCUCUACUAAAAAUACAAAAAUUAGGCAGGCGUGGUGGUGCACGCCUAUAAUCCCAGCUAUUUGGGAGGCUGAGGCAGGAGAAUCACUAGCAGAGAUUGUGUCUCCUCACCCCCUCUCAAAAAAAAAAAAAAAAAAAAAGUUCGUUCCUGCAGCAGUUAAAGCUGUGAAAGACAGGCACUCUGACAUGCAAUUCCUUGUGAUUUUUCUUUUUCCUUUUUGGAGUUGGGGUCUUGCGCUGUCACCCAGACUGGGGUGCAGUGGUGUGGUCAUAGCUCACUGCGGCCUCAGACUCAAGCUCAAGCGAUCCUCUUACCUUGCCUUUCAAAUUGCUGGGAUUAUAAGCAUGAGCCACUGCAUCUGGCCUGUGUGACACAAUUUUUUUUUUGUCUUUUUUCUUUUUGGGGGGGAUGGAGUCUCGCUCUGUCACCCAGGCUGGAGUGCGGUGGCGUGAUCUUGGCUCAAUGCAAGCUCUGCCUCCUGGGUUCACGCCAUUCUCCUGCCUCAGCCUCCCGAGUAGCUGGGACUACAGGCGCCCGCCACCAUGCCUGGCUAAUUUUUUGAAUUUUUAGUAGAGACGGGAUUUCACUGUCUUAGCCAGGAUGGUCUCGAUCUCCUGACCUCGUGAUCUGCCCGCCUUGGCCUCCCAAAGUGCUAGGAUUACAGGCGUGAGCCACCGCGCCCAGCCUAUGUGAUGCAAUUCUGAUGUCAACUCCCUGAUGUUACCUCAAAUGCCACAGGUUAAGGCCACCAGUCCCCACUAGGCUGCCCUCGCUUUAGACACACCUGCAGGCUUGGGUGUCCUCAGACCACAUGUACUUCUCACCAACUGGCUGCAAAUUUGGAGGUUCCCACCAUGCCCUCAAGUUCGAUAACUCACUAAAACAAUUCACAGAAUGCAGAAAAGCAUGAUACUUUCUUUCUC